AGUUGAGCCCUGAGGCCCUGCUGGCCCCUGGGCGCAGGCCCAGCUCAGGCCCCCAGGGAUGGACGUCGUGGACCCUGACAUUUUCAAUAGAGACCCCCGGGACCACUAUGACCUGCUACAGCGGCUGGGUGGCGGCACGUAUGGGGAAGUCUUUAAGGCUCGAGACAAGGUGUCAGGGGACCUGGUGGCACUGAAGAUGGUGAAGAUGGAGCCUGAUGAUGAUGUCUCCACCCUUCAGAAGGAAAUCCUCAUAUUGAAAACUUGCCGGCACGCCAACAUCGUGGCCUACCAUGGGAGUUAUCUCUGGUUGCAGAAACUCUGGAUCUGCAUGGAAUUCUGUGGGGCUGGUUCUCUCCAGGACAUCUACCAAGUGACAGGCUCCCUGUCAGAGCUCCAGAUUAGCUAUGUCUGCCGGGAAGUGCUCCAGGGACUGGCCUAUUUGCACUCACAGAAGAAGAUACACAGGGACAUCAAGGGAGCUAACAUCCUCAUCAAUGAUGCUGGGGAGGUCAGAUUGGCUGACUUUGGCAUCUCGGCCCAGAUUGGGGCUACACUGGCCAGACGCCUCUCUUUCAUUGGGACACCCUACUGGAUGGCUCCGGAAGUGGCAGCUGUGGCCCUGAAGGGAGGAUACAAUGAGCUGUGUGACAUCUGGUCCCUGGGCAUCACGGCCAUCGAACUGGCCGAGCUACAGCCACCGCUCUUUGAUGUGCACCCUCUCAGAGUUCUCUUCCUCAUGACCAAGAGUGGCUACCAGCCUCCCCGACUGAAGGAAAAAGGCAAAUGGUCGGCUGCCUUCCACAACUUCAUCAAAGUCACUCUGACUAAGAGUCCCAAGAAACGACCCAGCGCCACCAAGAUGCUCAGUCAUCAACUGGUAUCCCAGCCUGGGCUGAAUCGAGGCCUGAUCCUGGAUCUUCUUGACAAACUGAAGAAUCCCGGGAAAGGACCCUCCAUUGGGGACAUUGAGGAUGAGGAGCCCGAGCUACCCCCUGCUAUCCCUCGGCGGAUCAGAUCCACCCACCGCUCCAGCUCUCUGGGGAUCCCAGAUGCAGACUGCUGUCGGCGGCACAUGGAGUUCAGGAAGCUCCGAGGAAUGGAGACCAGACCCCCAGCCAACACCGCUCGCCUACAGCCUCCUCGAGACCUCAGGAGCAGCAGCCCCAGGAAGCAACUGUCAGAGUCGUCUGACGAUGACUAUGACGACGUGGACAUGCUGAACCUUGGCACCUGGAAAUCUCCCAAAGACCAGAUACUGAGCCCCAGAUCCAGACCCAACAGUCAGCCCAGGCCCCCAUACUCCCCAGCCCACAGGCCGAGUCAGGCUCCAUCCAGCCCCACCCCUGCAGAGGACACACCUCCUCCACUUCCCCCCAAGCCCAAGUUCCGUUCUCCAUCAGACGAGGGUCCUGGGAGCAUGGGGGAUGAUGGGCAGCUGAGCCCGGGGGUGCUGGUCCGGUGUGCCAGUGGGCCCCCACCAAACAGCCCCCGUCCUGGGCCUCCCCCAUCCACCAGCAGCCCCCACCUCACCGCCCAUUCAGAACCCUCACUCUGGAACCCACCCUCCCGGGAGCUUGACAAGCCCCCACUUCUGCCCCCCAAGAAGGAAAAGAUGAAGAGAAAGGGAUGUGCCCUUCUCGUAAAGUUGUUCAAUGGCUGCCCCCUCCGGAUCCACAGCACGGCCGCCUGGACACAUCCCUCCACCAAGGACCAGCACCUGCUCCUGGGGGCAGAGGAAGGCAUCUUCAUCCUGAACCGGAAUGACCAGGAGGCCACGCUGGAAAUGCUCUUUCCUAGCCGGACUACGUGGGUGUACUCCAUCAACAACGUUCUCAUGUCUCUCUCAGGAAAGACCCCCCACCUGUAUUCUCAUAGCAUCCUUGGCCUGCUGGAACGGAAAGAGACCAGAGCAGGAAACCCCAUCGCUCACAUUAGCCCCCACCGCCUACUGGCAAGGAAGAACAUGGUUUCCACCAAGAUCCAGGACACCAAAGGCUGCCGGGCGUGCUGUGUGGCGGAGGGUGCGAGCUCUGGGGGCCCGUUCCUGUGCGGUGCAUUGGAGACGUCCGUUGUCCUGCUUCAGUGGUACCAGCCCAUGAACAAAUUCCUGCUUGUCCGGCAGGUGCUGUUCCCACUGCCGACGCCUCUGUCCGUGUUCGCGCUGCUGACCGGGCCAGGCUCUGAGCUGCCCGCUGUGUGCAUCGGCGUGAGCCCCGGGCGGCCGGGGAAGUCGGUGCUCUUCCACACGGUGCGCUUUGGCGCGCUCUCUUGCUGGCUGGGCGAGAUGAGCACCGAGCACAGGGGACCCGUGCAGGUGACCCAGGUAGAGGAAGAUAUGGUGAUGGUGUUGAUGGAUGGCUCUGUGAAGCUGGUGACCCCGGAGGGGUCCCCAGUCCGGGGACUUCGCACACCUGAGAUCCCCAUGACCGAAGCGGUGGAGGCCGUGGCUAUGGUUGGAGGUCAGCUUCAGGCCUUCUGGAAGCAUGGAGUGCAGGUGUGGGCUCUAGGCUCGGAUCAGCUGCUACAGGAGCUGAGAGACCCUACCCUCACUUUCCGUCUGCUUGGCUCCCCCAGGCCUGUAGUGGUGGAGACACGCCCAGUGGAUGAUCCUACUGCUCCCAGCAACCUCUACAUCCAGGAAUGAGUCCCUAGGGGGGUGUCAGGAACUAGUCCUUGCACCCCCUCCCCCAUAGACACACUAGUGGUCAUGGCAUGUCCUCAUCUCCCAAUAAACAUGACUUUAGCCUCUGC